GUGGAGCUGCUGUCUAGACGCAGAUCAUGGGUGGCGGGUAUGAUCUCAACCUCUUCGCCAGCCCUCCUGACAGCAACUUCGUGUGCUCCGUCUGCCAUGGGGUUCUCAAGAGGCCAGCAAGGUUGCCAUGCAGCCACAUCUUCUGCAAAAAGUGCAUCCUCCGGUGGCUAGCCAGGGGUGGGGCAGGGCUAGGAGAGAAGGCAGGAGAAUCCCAUCUUCAGAGAGAAACAAGUGCAGCCUUGGGACGACCAGACAUAGCUGAGUUUGGAUCGUGGCUCUACUGCUUAGUUGCUGUGUGACUUUAGUGCAAGAACGCCGACGCUGGCUGCAUAGUGACAUGCCCCCUGGCCCAUCGCAAGGGGCACCAGGACUCAUGCCCCUUUGAGCUAACGGCCUGCCCCAACGAGGGCUGCACCUCGCAGGUGCCGCGUGGGACCCUGGCAGAGCACCGGCAGCAUUGCCAGCAAGGGUCCCAGCAGCGCUGCCCCCUGGGCUGCGGGGCCACCCUGGACCCGGCCGAGCGUGCUCGCCACAACUGCUACCGGGAGCUGCACAACGCCUGGAGCGUGCGCCAGGAGCGCCGUCGGCCCCUGCUGCUGUCCCUCCUGCGGCGUGUGCGCUGGCUGGACCAAGCCACCAGUGUCGUUCGUAGAGAGCUGGCGGAGCUCAGCAACUUCCUGGAGGAAGACACCGCUCUGCUGGAGGGUGCCCCACAGGAGGAGGCCGAGGCUGCCCCAGAAGGCAACGUUGGGGCUGAGGUGGUGGGGGAGCCCAGGGCCAACAUACCUUGUAAAUAGGUAAAUAAAAGCAGACCCCCGGCC